AAGACAAGAGAGAGGAAGCUUGAAGCCAAUAUGGAGUCCGUCAGUUGCUCCGCUGCUGCUGUCAGGACCGGAGACAUGGAGUCCCAGCGGGACCUGAGCCUGGUGCCUGAGCGGCUUCAGAGACGCGAACAAGAACGGCAGCUGGAAGUUGAAAGGCGGAAACAAAAGCGGCAGAACCAGGAGGUAGAGAAGGAGAACAGCCACUUUUUCGUCGCCACCUUUGUUCGGGAGCGAGCGGCCGUGGAAGAGCUUCUGGAGCGCGCGGAGUCGGUCGAGCGGCUGGAGGAGGCGGCCUCUCGGCUCCAGGGGCUGCAGAAACUAAUCAACGACUCAGUUUUUUUCCUAGCCGCUUACGACCUGCGGCAGGGACAAGAGGCGCUGGCGCGGCUGCAGGCGGCCUUGGCCGAGCGGCGCCGGGGGCUGCAGCCCAAGAAGCGUUUCGCUUUCAAGACCCGGGGAAAGGAUGCUGCUUCGUCUACCAAAGUAGACGCGGCUCCUGGCAUCCCCCCGGCAGUUGAAAGCAUACAGGACUCCCCGCUGCCCAAGAAGGCGGAAGGAGACCUCGGCCCCAGCUGGGUCUGCGGUUUCUCCAACCUGGAGUCCCAAGUCUUGGAGAAGAGAGCCAGCGAGUUGCACCAGCGCGACGUUCUUUUGACCGAACUGAGCAACUGCACGGUCAGACUGUAUGGAAAUCCCAACACCCUGCGGCUAACCAAGGCCCACAGCUGCAAGCUGCUCUGCGGUCCGGUGUCUACCUCUGUUUUCCUGGAGGACUGCAGUGACUGCGUGCUGGCAGUGGCCUGCCAACAGCUCCGCAUACACAGUACGAAAGACACCCGCAUCUUCCUGCAGGUGACCAGCAGGGCCAUCGUGGAGGACUGCAGUGGGAUCCAGUUCGCCCCUUACACCUGGAGCUACCCGGAGAUCGACAAGGACUUCGAGAGCUCUGGUUUAGAUAGGAGCAAAAAUAACUGGAACGAUGUUGACGAUUUUAACUGGCUGGCCCGGGAUAUGGCCUCCCCAAACUGGAGUAUUCUUCCUGAAGAGGAGCGAAAUAUCCAGUGGGACUAAGCAGUUGUCACUCUGUUCUUCACUCCUACCAAAUACUUUCCACGUUGGACUUUCCCCCUUAUUGGGUCUCGAAGUUUACUUAUUGUCACACUGUGUAUGUUUUCAGCAUUUUAAGGCUAGAGAUUGUAAUGGGCUCCUACUUGUAAUUUCCAUUAAAUUCGUAACAGGUAUAACACUAAAGCAUUUUUGCUAUUUUCGUCAUGCCUUUGAGACUGAGUCUUACUCCGUCCCCCAGCGUGGUGGCGCGCUGGGAUUACAGGCGCGCGCCACCACGCGAACUUGUAUUUUUAGUAGAGACGGGGUUUCGCCAUGUUGUCCGGGCUGCUCUCGAACUCCUGACCUCAGGUGAUCCACCCGCUUCAGCUUCCCAAAGUGCUGGCAUUACAGGCGUGAGCCACCACGCCAGGGCUUUAUUUAUUUAUUUUUACCACAAUAGUUUGAAGCAGUAAGGGGGAAGGAGGGUGAUUAUAUUGCUUUGUAAUGGUUUGUGAUACUUGAAACAUCACGGUGCAUAAUAAAGUAGGUCUGCAGUAAA